GUGCCUGUAGUUCUUCCGCCUACUGUAUCAUAGCAGCUUAGAAUCCCAGCUGCUGGCUCGGGCUGCAGUUCUCUCAUGGCUCGCACAGGGUGGACCAGCCCCAUUCCCCUAUGUGUUUCUCUGCUGCUGACCUGUGGCUUUGCUGAGGCAGGGAAGCUGCUGGUAGUGCCCAUGGAUGGGAGUCACUGGUUCACCAUGCAGUCGGUGGUGGAGAAACUUAUCCUCAGGGGGCAUGAGGUGGUUGUAGUCAUGCCAGAGGUGAGUUGGCAACUGGGAAAAUCACUGAAUUGCACAGUGAAGACUUACUCAACCUCAUACACUCUGGAGGAUCUGGACCGGGAAUUCAUGGAUUUCGCCGAUGCUCAAUGGAAAGCACAAGUACGAAGUUUGUUUUCUCUAUUUCUGAGUUCAUCCAAUGGUUUUUUUAACUUAUUUUUUUCGCAUUGCAGGAGUUUGUUUAAUGACCGAAAAUUAGUAGAAUACUUAAAGGAGAGUUCUUUUGAUGCGGUGUUUCUUGAUCCUUUUGAUGCCUGUGGCUUAAUUGUUGCCAAAUAUUUCUCCCUCCCCUCUGUGGUCUUCGCCAGGGGAAUAGCUUGCCACUAUCUUGAAGAAGGUGCACAGUGCCCUGCUCCUCUUUCCUAUGUCCCCAGAAUUCUCUUAGGGUUCUCAGAUGCCAUGACUUUCAAGGAGAGAGUACGGAACCACAUCAUGCACUUGGAGGAACAUUUAUUUUGCCAGUAUUUUUCCAAAAAUGCCCUAGAAAUAGCCUCUGAAAUUCUCCAAACACCUGUCACAGCAUAUGAUCUCUACAGCCACACAUCAAUUUGGUUGUUGCGAACAGACUUUGUUUUGGACUAUCCCAAACCCGUGAUGCCCAAUAUGAUCUUCAUUGGUGGUAUCAACUGCCAUCAGGGAAAGCCAUUGCCUAUGGAAUUUGAAGCCUACAUUAAUGCUUCUGGAGAACAUGGAAUUGUGGUUUUCUCUUUGGGAUCAAUGGUCUCAGAAAUUCCAGAGAAGAAAGCUAUGGCAAUUGCUGAUGCUUUGGGCAAAAUCCCUCAGACAGUCCUGUGGCGGUACACUGGAACCCGACCAUCGAAUCUUGCGAACAACACGAUACUUGUUAAGUGGCUACCCCAAAACGAUCUGCUUGGUCACCCGAUGACCCGUGCCUUUAUCACCCAUGCUGGUUCCCAUGGUGUUUAUGAAAGCAUAUGCAAUGGCGUUCCCAUGGUGAUGAUGCCCUUGUUUGGUGAUCAGAUGGACAAUGCAAAGCGCAUGGAGACUAAGGGAGCUGGAGUGACCCUGAAUGUUCUGGAAAUGACUUCUGAAGAUUUAGAAAAUGCUCUAAAAGCAGUCAUCAAUGACAAAAGUUACAAGGAGAACAUCAUGCGCCUCUCCAGCCUUCACAAGGACCGCCCGGUGGAGCCGCUGGACCUGGCCGUGUUCUGGGUGGAGUUUGUGAUGAGGCACAAGGGCGCGCCACACCUGCGCCCCGCAGCCCACGACCUCACCUGGUACCAGUACCAUUCCUUGGACGUGAUUGGUUUCCUCUUGGCCGUCGUGCUGACAGUGGCCUUCAUCACCUUUAAAUGUUGUGCUUAUGGCUACCGGAAAUGCUUGGGGAAAAAAGGGCGAGUUAAGAAAGCCCACAAAUCCAAGACCCAUUGAGAAGUGGGUGGGAAAUAAGGUAAAAUUUUGAACCAUUCCCUAGUCAUUUCCAAACUUGAAAACAGAAUCAGUGUUAAAUUCAUUUUAUUCUUAUUAAGGAAAUACUUUGCAUAAAUUAAUCAGCCCCAGAGUGCUUUAAAAAAUUCUCUUAAAUAAAAAUAAUAGACUCGCUAGUCAGUAAAGAUAUUUGAAUAUGUAUCGUGCCCCCUCUGGUGUCUUUGAUCAGGAUGACAUGUGCCAUUUUUCAGAGGACGUGCAGACAGGCUGGCAUUCUAGAUUACUUUUCUUACUCUGAAACAUGGCCUGUUUGGGAGUGCGGGAUUCAAAGGUGGUCCCACGGCUGCCCCUACUGCAAAUGGCAGUUUUAAUCUUAUCUUUUGGCUUCUGCAGAUGGUUGCAAUUGAUCCUUAACCAAUAAUGGUCAGUCCUCAUCUCUGUCGUGCUUCAUAGGUGCCACCUUGUGUGUUUAAAGAAGGGAAGCUUUGUACCUUUAGAGUGUAGGUGAAAUGAAUGAAUGGCUUGGAGUGCACUGAGAACAGCAUAUGAUUUCUUGCUUUGGGGAAAAAGAAUGAUGCUAUGAAAUUGGUGGGUGGUGUAUUUGAGAAGAUAAUCAUUGCUUAUGUCAAAUGGAGCUGAAUUUGAUAAAAACCCAAAAUACAGCUAUGAAGUGCUGGGCAAGUUUACUUUUUUUCUGAUGUUUCCUACAACUAAAAAUAAAUUAAUAAAUUUAUAUAAAUUCUA